ACGCCUGGGCCCGGCCGCCCCGCUGCUCCGGCCGCGCGUCCCGCGUCGGUCCGACGGUCUGUCCGUCCUCCUGCCACCCCCCGCCCCCACGGGGCUUCUUUGUGCGGCGCUCCUCGCCGGCCGGUCCCACCUCCAGGCCUCGCCCCUCGCCGUCGCCACCGCCGGACUCUGCCCAGGGGAAUGGUCUGCGAGCCGGGUUUUUGGAGACAGGAAGUGAGGCGUGCGAGCCCCAUGAGCGCGCCGCGGCCCGGGCUGGCGUGCGGGUGCGGCUGCGGCGGCCGCGCGGCGGGGCCCCGGGAGGCGGGUCGCUGAGCGGGGCGCGCGGCCCCGAGGAUGCGGGAGCGGGAGCGGGAGCAGCGCUGGCGUCAAUGCUCCCUUCCUCGGGCCAUUGGAGACUCCGUUGCUUUUUAAUGGCGGCAGCGGCUGCUGGGUGAGCAGCUGGAGGCCGGACAGUGUUCGUCCCAUCCGGAGAGGAUCGCUUUCUCCUGGCGUCACCAGCGCUGGGUUGGUGGGGGUAGCUUUUCCCUCUUUGCUCCUCCAUUCUUGAAGAAAGAAGAAGAUGCCACUGCCAUUUGGGUUGAAACUGAAACGCACCCGGCGCUACACGGUGUCCAGCAAGAGUUGCCUGGUUGCCCGGAUCCAACUGCUUAAUAACGAGUUUGUGGAGUUCACCCUGUCCGUGGAGAGCACUGGCCAGGAAAGCCUCGAGGCCGUGGCCCAGAGGCUGGAGCUGCGGGAGGUCACUUACUUCAGCCUCUGGUACUACAACAAGCAAAAUCAGCGCCGGUGGGUAGAUUUGGAAAAACCUUUGAAGAAGCAGCUGGAUAAAUAUGCAUUGGAACCUACCGUCUAUUUUGGAGUGGUGUUUUAUGUGCCUUCAGUUUCUCAGCUGCAGCAGGAGAUUACCAGGUAUCAGUAUUAUCUGCAACUGAAGAAAGAUAUCUUGGAAGGAAGUAUUCCUUGUACCUUAGAACAAGCAAUUCAGCUAGCAGGCUUAGCUGUUCAAGCGGAUUUUGGUGACUUUGAUCAGUAUGAAUCCCAGGACUUUCUUCAGAAAUUUGCCUUGUUUCCUGUGGGAUGGUUACAAGAUGAAAAAGUAUUGGAAGAAGCAACCCAAAAAGUGGCCUUACUACAUCAGAAAUACAGAGGGCUCACAGCUCCUGAUGCUGAAAUGCUGUACAUGCAGGAGGUAGAGAGAAUGGAUGGCUAUGGAGAAGAGAGCUACCCUGCUAAGGAUAGCCAAGGAAGUGACAUAUCCAUUGGAGCGUGUCUUGAAGGUAUCUUUGUGAAACACAAGAAUGGAAGGCAUCCUGUGGUAUUUAGGUGGCAUGACAUUGCCAACAUGUCCCACAACAAGUCCUUUUUUGCAUUAGAGCUGGCAAAUAAAGAGGAGACCAUUCAAUUUCAAACUGAAGACAUGGAAACAGCAAAAUACAUUUGGAGACUCUGUGUUGCGCGACACAAGUUUUACAGACUAAACCAGUGUAACCUGCAAACUCAGACUGUCACAGUGAACCCAAUCAGGAGGAGGUCUUCUUCAAGGAUGUCUCUGCCUAAACCCCAGCCCUACGUGAUGCCUCCCCCACCGCAGUUGCACUAUAAUGGACAUUAUACAGAACCAUAUGCUUCUUCCCAAGAUAACCUCUUUGUGCCCAACCAGAACGGAUACUACUGUCACUCUCAGACAAGCUUGGAUAGAGCCCAGAUUGACCUCAACGGUCGGAUCCGUAAUGGCAGUGUCUACAGUGCACACAGCACCAACUCCUUAAAUAAUCCUCAGCCCUACUUGCAGCCCUCGCCGAUGUCGUCCAACCCUAGCAUCACCGGGAGUGACGUCAUGAGGCCUGACUACCUCCCGUCCCAUCGGCACAGCGCCGUGAUACCCCCGUCCUACCGCCCCACCCCAGACUAUGAGACUGUGAUGAAGCAGCUCAACAGGGGCCUGGUGCAUGCGGAACGGCAGAGCCACUCGCUGCGAAACCUCAACAUCGGCAGCUCGUACGCCUACAGCAGGCCCGCGGCGCUGGUCUACAGCCAGCCCGAGAUCCGCGAGCACGCACAGCUCCCCUCGCCAGCGGCCGCACACUGCCCGUUCAGCCUGAGCUACAGCUUCCACAGCCCGUCUCCCUACCCCUACCCUGCCGAGCGGCGGCCCGUGGUGGGCGCGGUCAGCGUGCCGGAGCUGACCAAUGCGCAGCUGCAGGCGCAGGACUACCCGUCUCCCAACAUCAUGCGGACGCAGGUGUACCGGCCACCCCCACCCUACCCGCCCCCCAGGCCCGCCAACAGCACGCCAGACCUGUCCCGCCACCUUUACAUCAGCAGCAGCAACCCCGACCUCAUCACGCGGCGCGUGCACCACUCGGUGCAAACGUUCCAGGAGGACAGCCUGCCCGUGGCGCACUCGCUGCAGGAGGUCAGCGAGCCCCUCACCGCCGCGCGCCACGCGCAGCUGCACAAACGGAACAGCAUCGAGGUGGCCGGGCUCAGCCACGGCCUGGAGGGCCUGCGGCUCAAGGAGCGCACCCUAUCCGCGUCGGCGGCAGAGGUGGCGCCGCGAGCCGUCUCGGUGGGCUCCCAGCCCAGCGUUUUCACCGAGAGGACACAGCGAGAAGGGCCGGAGGAGGCGGAGGGCUUGAGGUACGGCCAUAAGAAGUCCCUGUCGGACGCCACCAUGCUAAUCCACAGCAGCGAGGAGGAGGAGGACGAGGACUUCGAGGAGGAGAGCGGGGCCCGGGCGCCUCCUGCACGUGCGCGCGAGCCUCGGCCCGGCCUGGCCCAGGACCCACCUGGCUGCCCUCGCGUCCUGCUCGCCGGGCCCCUGCACAUCCUGGAGCCCAAGGCCCACGUCCCAGACGCGGAGAAGAGGAUGAUGGACAGCAGCCCCGUCCGCACGACCGCAGAGGCCCAGCGGCCCUGGAGAGACGGGCUGCUGAUGCCCUCCAUGUCGGAGUCCGACCUCACCACGUCAGGCCGCUACCGAGCCCGGAGGGACUCUCUGAAGAAAAGGCCGGUGUCGGACCUUCUCUCUGGGAAGAAGAACAUCGUGGAAGGGCUCCCGCCUCUAGGGGGAAUGAAAAAGACUCGAGUAGAUGCAAAAAAAAUUGGUCCUCUUAAACUGGCUGCCCUAAAUGGACUCUCCCUAUCUCGAGUGCCUCUGCCUGAUGAAGGAAAGGAAGUGGCUACCAGAGCAACGAAUGAUGAAAGGUGUAAAAUUCUGGAACAACGAUUAGAACAAGGAAUGGUAUUCACAGAAUAUGAAAGAAUUCUUAAGAAACGGCUAGUUGAUGGGGAGUGCUCAACAGCACGACUCCCUGAAAAUGCAGAAAGAAAUCGAUUCCAAGAUGUUCUUCCUUAUGAUGAUGUGAGAGUGGAGUUGGUCCCAACUAAAGAAAACAACACUGGUUACAUCAACGCAUCACAUAUUAAGGUCUCUGUCAGUGGAAUCGAAUGGGAUUAUAUUGCCACACAGGGACCAUUACAGAAUACCUGUCAAGAUUUUUGGCAGAUGGUAUGGGAACAGGGAAUUGCAAUUAUAGCAAUGGUGACAGCAGAAGAGGAGGGUGGAAGGGAGAAGAGCUUUAGGUACUGGCCACGACUUGGUUCCAGGCACAACACUGUCACCUAUGGAAGGUUUAAGAUCACGACCCGGUUCCGCACAGACUCUGGCUGCUAUGCCACCACAGGCCUGAAGAUGAAGCACCUCCUUACUGGGCAAGAGAGGACCGUCUGGCACCUCCAAUACACAGACUGGCCUGAACAUGGCUGUCCAGAAGACCUCAAGGGAUUUUUAUCAUAUCUUGAAGAGAUCCAGUCUGUUCGACGCCAUACAAAUAGCACAAGUGAUCCCCAAAGCCCCAACCCUCCGUUGUUGGUCCACUGCAGUGCUGGGGUAGGAAGGACUGGCGUGGUGAUUUUGUCGGAGAUCAUGAUCGCCUGCCUGGAACACAAUGAGGUGCUGGACAUCCCGAGAGUGCUGGACAUGCUGAGGCAACAGAGAAUGAUGCUGGUGCAGACUCUCUGCCAGUACACAUUUGUGUACAGAGUCCUCAUCCAGUUCCUGAAAAGCUCCAGGCUCAUCUAAGCUCCCACAAUUUCUUACGGGGCCAGUCAUGUGAAGCGUUUACAGCUUAAAAAAAAAGCGCUUGCCUAACUCAUACUUUCCCGUUGACACUUGAUCCACGCAGCGUGGCACUGGGACGUAAGUGGCGCAGUCUGAAUGGCGGCACGCUGAAGGAAACGUGCGAAGCACAGGCUGAAGAGGGGUUUCUAACCUGGGAAAGGUGCUCAAGGAGGACUUGGUUUCAAGGGCCUUGCCCUGCCCCGGUCUGUCCGGUUUGCAGUACUUGCACACAUUUUGGAGAUUGUAUUUUCUAGACAAUUCUCUAUUUUACUGAAGCUAUGCUGGGCAAUUCUGGCAAUCAUUAAAGUGCAUAGAUUUCUAUCUUAAACUAAUUUUUGAUAAUGGAGUUUUUAUUUUAUGACAAAUAUUUAGGGAUUUUUCUAGUGAGAAACAACUUUGUGUAAGGAUGAUCCACAGAUAUGAGUUGCUCCUAUAUAACUUUGUAUUUAAAAAUCAUGUUAUUAUCUUUUGUUAUUUUUUAAAAACCUUGGGUACUUAAUAAUGGUUUAGUUGCCAAACUGAAAACUAUACUGAGAAUCUGUGUUAUUUUGAAACAUCAAAAGGAUUUUUCUAUCCAGAACAUUUUUUAUCCUAAAAAUUCUAUAUAGUUGUACCUUCUGUUUUUCAAAUGAGAGCUCAAUUCAUUUAGAUACUGAAAUGAGUCAGUUAAUGUAAAGUUGAGGAUGAAGGCACAUUAUUUAAAAUGUAAGAGAAUAAGCAUUAUUUUUUCAGUAUUAUUCAUAGAUCUAAAUGAAUUUGAUUUUAUUGGUUGAAAAUGAAGUGAAAAACAAUUGCCUAGGGUGGUUUUAAGCACUUUUUUGUUAAAAACAAAUCUGAGUUUUAAUAUAUGUGUUGCUUUGUAGAUGACACAAUAACAAUGGGCGCUGAGAAGCGUUUUGGGAGAGAUUAAGGACUAAGAGUAUGUAAGAUGACUAGGACAAGAGUAGGUGGAGUGUGAUGGUAAAUGCAGGAUGCCUUCGUCUUUACAAAAAUGCAGUAUUAUCUAUACUCAGACUGAGGUGCUGGGAUGGCGAGCAGGGGACCCCACAGCACUGUCCCCAGGGAAUUCAAGUCCUGUGACCGCCAGUGACUUACUCCGUUUCCUUGGGGCUUUUCCCACCUCAACCUGUAUUGUUUCUUUUUCAUAAAUAAAUUCAGCAUUAUAGUAUCAUUAAAAGAAGCCUUAAAGAGGCGUAUUUUUCCUUUUGGUUGAAGGAAGGGAAUAGUUAAUAAUAGUUUUCACCUCUUCUCCCAAAAAGUACAGUCCAAAUUUGUGCACAGAGAUUGCUGUGGUAUUCAAGAGGUACUUGCAUUUUAGCUCCUUAAUAAUUCCCUGGCCAGUGUUAGCUGUUUAGUGCCCCCUCACCCAUCCCAUUUAGGCACAUCCCAAUAGACAGAGCCAGGCUGAGUUACAGGGGGAGAGUGUCAUCUCUGGCCCCGAUUAAGAUGGCCUUGUCACAGUGACCGCUGAGUAGGCAUGGAUGAGUGGGAUAUUUAGCUGAGGAACCCUUUCCCUUUUCCUUCUUUUUGGGGUCUCUUCUUACAGUGAACUUCCAAAAUGUCAAAUCUAGGGCUGUUUCCCAAAUUACACUAUUCUAGGCAUCAUUUUGAUUCCCAUGUCACUCCUUAACUCACUUCCUUGAGCACUACAUGUAUGUUGUCAGCCACGAGACAGGACUUCCUAAAUAGUGUGUGCACCAGCCUAACUCUGCCUUACCCAGAAACCAACCACCUAAGAGGAAAACUCAGAAGAUAUUAAUGAAAACUAAUUGAAAGUACGCACACUUCUCAUGUAGGAACAAAAUUAAAAUUUUACAUUUUUAUUUUACAAAAUUAAAAAAUUACAUUUUGUAGGAACAAAAUGUAAAUUUUGUAAAUACAAAAUUCUUUUUAAAGUCCUGUUUAAAGAACAGUAGAACUAAGUGAAAAUAUUCAGAACGAGCUCCUUAGAAGAAAGGAAUAAGAACUUUUUACUGGAACUAUUUUCCAUCUCUAGAAAAAGUGCUUCUUCCCCUCCCCCUCCCUCUCCAUGGUACGUUUUUGUGAAAAUGCUUUUCUGUCAGGUUUAAACAAACAGUUUGACAUAGCUCGUUGACAAGAACAUAUUGUAAAACAAAUCUAAUUAAAGAGUAAUAUGUGGUCUAUUUGUGUUCCUGUUGUAAUAAUUUGAUAAGUAAACUUCUGAGGGCAAAAUUACUGUUUAAUAUUACUCUUAAAAUGUUGCAUGUUUGGCGUCAUUCCUAAGAGCCAUGUAAUUUUAAACUUUUAAUUGCAGUUAGUGAAUAUGAAAGGAUUUCUGAAUAAAAAUCUAUCCACAUUA